AGUCAGUGAUAGUUGUGAUUUCAUUGGAGGAGUCUAUGGCAAGGUUGACUUCAACUCCAGGUAAUAAUUGCAAAGCACCUCUCUGAUACUUUGUACUGAGAUUCAUUUAACUCUUCUUUUGUCUCUGUCCUUACACUAGUAUUUUCAGGCUUCUGCAUUUGCUUUGCUUUUGCUUUGAAGUAUGUGUGUAAUUUUGGUAUAGUGCCCCCAUCUUCAUUGUUUAGGAACUUUUAAAAAACACUUUCUAGUGAGUUUAUUGAAGUCAUAGAUUGAAGAUUGCUUGAGAUUAGCAGUUUUGUAGACUUCGGGGGGAUCUUGGUUGAGUUGUGAUGUAUAUAUGUUCUAUCUUAAGUUGCAAUCUGAAUUUUUAGAUAAAUGACUGUUUUUCUUUUUUUAAAAAUCUGUUUGAGCUGUGAAAUGGGAGCAUGAGGAGAGCUGAAAUGGUAUGAGAGUGGAAUUUGAUGGAAAGUUUGUCAUGAUUAAUAAUGUGACUAUGUGCCUCUUAUCAGUCCUUACCGUUGUAUUAUCAUUGUUAUUGGUCCGUAUCAGUGCACAAAUGAAGUAUGAAUAUCCUGAAGAUUUUUUGUUGACAUCUCAGAUUUGAGCCUUUUGGUUCACUGACCAUAUUAGAUUUUCUCUAUGGAAGACAAAUAGACUCAUUCCCAUAAUAAAGAACUAGAGCGCUGAUAGAGCACACUUUUUUUUUUCCCCUUUGGAUCAAAUCAUGGAAGUUCAAAUCUGAAAAUAAAUUCAGAAAUUUCUUUUUUUCCCCAUAGCAUCCCUAUAUUCCUAACCUUUUGAGUGGUGAGUCAAGCAAUAUUUAUUGAAUGCUGCUAUCUGGCAGGUGCACUUUUGGUUUCUGUGAUUACAGUGAUGAGCAAGAGUGUACCUGGCCACAUGGAACUUGUAGUCCAGUGGGACCAUUUGUAGUAAUAUUUUCUGGCAUGGAGUUAUGGUACCCUGAUGCCCUCGUAAAGGUUAUACAUAAUAGGCAAUUAUUUUUGAAUUUUAAUAUAUUUUAACAUUUUGAAAUAAUGUAACCUAGAAUUUGUCCUCAGAAGGUCUGGGUUUCAAAUACCUGCCCUGCCAUUUUCGUUGUGAGAUAUUGAAAAAUAAUUGAACUUCUUUCUGAACUUUACUGUUGUUUCCUGCGGAGAUGGGCUCAAGACUUGCUUCACAGAUGAGCUACAAAAAUUGAUGAGAAUACAUGUAUGAAAGUACUUUGUAAACUAUAAAGUCUUAUUUGUAAUAGGGUUUUCUUACUUUUUGUUGGACAGAUUCAUGGAUUGUUGGAACUAGGAGGGAUUUUGACUCAUUUGGCUCAUGUUUCCCAUUUUACGUAUGAGGAAACUGAAGCCCAGAAAGUUGAAGUGAUUUGUUGAAGGUUAUAGAACUGGUUAAUGACUAGGCAGUGAUUGGAAGACAGGUGUCCAUAUUUAAUUGCACUCGUUUCUUUUCUUUUUUUCCUACCUUAGAGCCUGUUAUGUUAAAAUUUUACUACUUUCUCCCCCCACUUAAGAGUUCAGUAUUUAUUAAAUAUCCAAAAUGAGGAGAUGCAAAACUUAAGGAAACGAACGAUCUGUGGUGAGGUUGUAAAGCUAUGAAAACAACAUUGGUAACCGAGCUUCAUAAUUAAAUGACAAAGUUACAGAAAAAGAAAAUAUGAGUUAAAGUUUCUACAUAGUAGAGCCUGUAGGCUUUUUUGUUUUGUUUCAUUUUUAAAGAAAUCUUUAUUUGCACAGAGCAUAAUGUACUCUUUAGCUCUUUAGAAAAGCUAAACUCAGUUUAUUUUGGUUCAUCUUUUUCUUCUCUUUUUAAACUCAUUUCCAUUUGCGGAAGAAAUUAGGUGUACCAUCCUUGUUUCUGGACCAUGGCCAACUAAAUUUUAGACCUUUUUUCUCAGCGACAUGUAAGGGUAACCAGAGAUUGGGGCUGGGGGUGUUAGGUGGAGAGAUAAAACAGGACAUAAAACAGGAACGUGUAGGAGCUUCCUGUUGAAAAUGGGACUGAUUUAUGUUGCGCCACCCUACCUUCCAGUGGAGUAAUCUGAGCCAGCAGAGAAGAAACUUCCCUGCUGGUUGGGUGAAUGCCCUUGAGGUGAGGGGGUUUCCUUCUUCCGGGAGAGAUAAGCAUUGUGGUAUUCUGCCAUUGCUCACACAGAAGUUUGGGUCUUAUUCUACAGACAGACGCAGUAAAAUAAGGGUGUUCCACUAUCCCUUGAGACUGACAAUCUGACCUUCUAUCUGCUGCACUUCUACUUUUUUGGUAUGGGAAAUCAAUUGGCCUCAUUGAAUUUUUGCUUUUAGUUUUUUUCUAUGCCUAGCUAAUCAAAAACAAAAACAAAACCCACAUGCUUUGAUGACACCUUGCUUUCAAAGGUUAUAUUUAAGUUAAUUAUUCUUAAAUGAUAGCUCAUUUAUUUUUAUUCAGUGGACUGUUGAUGAGCUCUGGAGUGAGUCUUAGAAGCAUGGGAAAGAUUUGUGGCUUCUGGGUCUUUUAAACAUGGAUGAUUUGCAUAAGGGACAGAGCAACACAGUGAUUUGGUUUGUGAUCAUGAGGGUACAAAAAACCAUCAGGGCAGAUCUUUUAAUGGUAGGUAAUGUUCACCAGUCAACAACCAUUUUCUCCUUUUAUUCUGGCCUGGAGAGAGUAAGAUAACCCCAUUUGCAAAUAGAACAGAGUGUUUUCUUAAAGGCAUAGAGAGAUGACACCAAAAUGACAUGGAGGGAUGUCAGGAGCUGCUUUAGCUGGCCCGUAGUAAGUAGUAGUGCAUUGGUGGGUGUGCCACAAAGUCAGGCGAAGCCAUUUCUCUUUGCCUCUGGAGUCUGGGAUGAGAAAUUUCAACCUGUAGAUUUCCAAUUUGUUGCUUGUCAUGUUGCACUAAGUUCUCCCUCUAAUUAGGAUUUAGUAUGCCUAAGUUGAAAUUGCGGGAAGCAGGCAAUUACAUAAUGUUAGAUUUCCCUUUUUCCAAUUCAGGAAAGGCAGGAGAAUGUGUGCUUGUUAUGAAUGCCAGCUUGGGGAGGGAGAAUUGCUGGUUCACACAAACUCGGGGGUCACUCAAAGGCAACUUGAGCAGAACUGACAGCCAGUGCUGCUGCCAUUGGAUUCCUUUUUUCCUCUUUCCUCCCACAGAGCAGGUCUAGGUUAAAUGAAUUUCACAGAUAUGAAAGUUAAUUGUGGUUAUUUCUUUUCUCUUUCUACUUUUUCCACAAAGCCUUUUACCAAAGCUAUGAACAGGUAUAGUCAUUGAUGGUUUUGUGGUUCAGCGACUUGCUUCUUUUUUUUUUUUUUUGAGAUGGAGUCUCGCUGUGUCACCCAGGCUGGAGUGCAGUGGCAUGACCUCGGCUCACUACAACCUCUGCCUCCUGGGUUCAAGCGAUUCUCCUGCCUCAGCCUCCCGAGUAGCUGGGAUUACAGGCACACGCCGCCACACCUGGCUGAUUUUUAUAUUUUUAGUAGAGGCAGGGUUUCGCCAUGUUGGCCAGGCUGGUCUCAAACUCCUGACCUUAGGUGAUCCGCCUGCCUCAGCCUCCCAAACUGCUGGGAUUACAGGCAGGAGCCACCACACCUGGCCGACUUGCUUCUUUUUAUAAUGAGUUCUGAACUGCUCAGAAAGAAGCUAUUGAGAAAGAAAAGCAAAGGGCUGUGUGCCAAACGAUCGUGUUCCUAUAAUCAAGACUUGACUAUGGUCAGUGUCUUUUACUCUGGCUCCAUGUUAUCUUUCUGUAAUUCAUUUUCUUCAUAUUGUAAAUUAUUUAUCUAGAUAGGAAAUGUAAUUUGCUUUUUUUUUUUUUUUUUUUUGAGAUGGAGUCUGUUACCCAGGCUGGUGUGCAGUGACACCAUCUCUGCUCACUGCAACCUCUGCCUCCUGGGUUCAAGCGAUUCUCCUGCCUCAGCCUCCCAAGUAGCUGGGAUUACAGGCGUGUGCCACCACACCCAGCUAAUUUUUGUUUUUUUAGUAAAGACAGGGUUUCGCCAUGUUGGCCAGGCUGGUCUAGGACUCCUGACUUCCAGCGAUCCUCCCGCCUUGGCCUCCCAAAGUGCUGGUAUUACAGAUGUGAGCCAUUGCGCCCGGCCUAAUUUGGUAUUUUUUGGGCUCAUUGCCUUUCCUUUAAUAGUCUCUAGCUCCCAGAAUUGAUUGAAAUCUUUUUUUUUUUUUUUUUUGAGACGGAGUUUUUGCUCUUGUCAUGCAGGCUGGAGUGCAGUGAUGUGAUCUCGGCUCACUGCAACCUCUGCCUCCCGGGUUCAAGCGAUUCUCCUGCAACAGCCUCCUGAGUAGCUGGAACUACAGGCGUGUGCCACCAUGCCCAGCUAAUUUUUUGUAUUUUUAGUAGAGAUGGGGUUUCACCAUAUUGGCCAGGCUGGUCUUGAACUCCUGACUUCAGGUGAUCCGCCCGCCUCGGCCUCCCAGUGUGCUGGGAUUACAGGCAUGAGCACCCGGCCUGAACCUCUAUUUUUACAUUUCUUUUCUAUUUUACGUUUCUUUUCAGUUCUUGAUGCUUAUCAUCAGUUCUUGAUGCUCUUAGCUGCUAACUGGACUGUGGUAUCCCAUGUCUUCAGGAAGAGAGAGUCUGCUUAUUAGGAGAUGCUUAUAAGAUAUAGAAAUAUAAAUUAAUAGGAUGUCCUAAAAUUUUCACCAAAUUUGACUUUUAUUGCUUGCUUCACCUGUAUAUACCUAGGAAUAAAAAUGGAGUCAGUUUUUUUCCAUAUUCUUGCAAGAAUCAUGGGGCUGUGGCUCUGAACCAUACUGCUUGACUUUUAAAGACUUUUCAGAAACACAUGUUCUUGAAAUGUGGGUUAAAUGUGUAGUUGAUUUAACUCCUCCCUUUUCCCUAACCAUACUUGUAGCUGCUCCACUGAAGACCUCAGAAGCUUCUGCCAGUAUGCUUUCCCAGAGCCUAACUUCUUAGUAGCUGGUAUUUGACAUACGAAGAGAGUGCUCUGUGUGCAUAUGUGUGCAUGCUUGUGUGUUUGUUUGUGUAGUGGGGGGCAGAUUUGACUCCUAGCUCAGAAUGUGCUCUUGUGAAACAUGUUAGGAAGCCUGAAUAUGGUUCCUAAACUGUGUCUCUUUUCCAGUUUGAGAAAUGCCUGUGAUUCUUCAAAGAGUCUCAGUAUUGUUUUAUUUUUUAAAUUAGGAUCUUAAUGAUGAGUCUCAGUAUUGUUUUAUUUUUUAAAUUAGGAUCUUAAUGAUGAUCCUUUGUAACAGGAAGCAAGGUAUAGUAAAUUGCAUAACAAAAUAAUGUUUCAGUAGAUAAAUGGUAGGUUACAGAGAGCUGUAGGAUUCACAGAAAAGGCUUAUUAAAAGUUCAGGAACCUCAGCCUAAUCUGGGUGAGAUUGUUCUGAAGGCCAUUUUCAAGGUGGUGGUUAAAAGUGCUGAUUUUCUGUGGUUUGGGUGGGAUGUGUGUUUGGGGAAGCAGUGAGUGCUUGAGUAGAGAAUCACAUGAACCUUGAGGCUUUUCUCCUGGGGGAGAAUGCUAGAUAUUGAGGUUGAUGGGUGAUUUGAAGAAGCUCAGUAGGUGAUUCUGUUAUGCUUCUCCCCCACCCAGUUGAAAACACAGUGGCUUUUAUAUAAUUUUUAGAUCUAUGCUUGACAAUAAGGUAAAUAAGUAGUGGACUUAAACCAGAAUGCAGCCAACUGAGGAUUGUAGAAACUUCAUUUUGGAUGGGUAAAAAGGAGAGCCUCUGGAUCUUUUGUAGAGGCCCAUUGAUUCAAAAAGAUAACUUGGAAUAACUCCUCAAAUGACUGCCAACAGUUUAAAGGGUCAGACUGCUUAGACUCCUGCAGUGGAGAUGGGACAUGUACAUGCAAUUUGAUAAUUGUAUGUUGGCACUUCUUUUAAAAAAAUUGUGGUAAAAACAGAAAAAGUUGACCAUUUCAACCAUUUUUAAGUAUAUAGUUCAGUAGUGUUAAGUAUAUUCACCUUGUCAUGAAACAGAUUUCCAGGACUUUUUCAUCUUGCGAAUCUGAAACUCUGUAAGCAUUAAACAUUGGCCCCCAUUUCCACCUCCCACAGACUCUGGCAACCAUCAUUCUUUCUGUUUCUAUGAAUCUGGCUACUUUAGGUAACCUCAUAUAAGUGGAAUCAUGUAGUAUUUGUCUGUGUCUGAAUUAUUUGACUUAGCAUAAAAUCCUCAAGGUUCAUCAAUGUUUGUAGCAUGUGACAGGAUUUCUAUCUUUUUAAAGGUUUAAUAGUAUUCCGUCGUAUGGGUAUACCACAUUUUGUUUAUCCAUUUAUCUGUGGAUAGAUAUUUGGCAGUUGUGAUUGUUGCUAUGAACGUGGGUGUGCAGAUAUCUCUUCAAGAUCCUGCUUUUAAUUAUUUUGUGUAUAUACCCAGAAGCGGGAUUGCUGGAUCAUAUGAUAGUUUUAUUUUUAAUUUUUUGAGGAACCUCCAUACUGUUUUUCGUAGUUGUACCAUUUUACAAUCUCAUCAACAGUUCAUAAGGGUUCUAACUUCUCCACAUCCUUACCAAUACUUAUUUUCUGUUUUUUUUUUUUUCAAAUUAAUUAAUAAAAAAUUUUUCGAGACAGGGUCUCCCUCUGCCACUCAGGUUGGGGUGCAGUGGUGCCAUCUCAGCUCACUGCAACGUCCACCUCCCGGGCUCAAGCAAUCCUCCUGCCUCAGCCUCCCGAGUAGCUGGGACUAAUGGUGUACACCACCACACCCAGAGCUAAUUAAAAAAACAAUUUAAAUAGGAACCAUCUUAAUGGAUGCAAGGUAGUAUCUCAUUAUGAUUUUGAUAUAUGUUUCUCUGAUGAUUGAUGAAGUUGAUUGUAUUUUCAUAUUCUCGUUGGCCAUUUGUAUAUUAUCUCUGCAUAUAUGUCUGUUCAAGCCUUCUGCCCAUUUUUAAAUUGGGUUAUUUGAUUUUUGUUGUUGAGUUGUAGGAGUUCUUUAUAUAUUCUGGGUAUAUAUUUUUUUCCUUCAGCAUUGUGUUUUACUUUUUUGGGGAGAGGCUAGGAGGAGGAAGGGGUGAAAACAGGUUCUCAUUGGAGUCUCCAAAGUGUAUGCAACCUCUGGCAAUACAAGGAUGGGAUGAGAUGGCCAGGCCAGUCAGAUAGAAAAUCCCCAAGAUUCUUUUGGCGACUGAUUUCUAUAAUUAAAAUAUGACAGGUGGAAAGGACUAGUACAUGGAAUUCAAUAAAUGUCAGUUGUCUUUCCUAACUAGGUUCCUCAUGGGCUAGGUUAUGCCUAGAUAUCAUCAUCCUUCUCCAAAUGAAGCUCGCCUAGAAAACUAGGGAACUAAAAGUGCAAUACAGUUUGGGUAAUGAAGUUGGUUAGCUGUCUCCCCAUCCUCCCAACUCCACUAUUCCAGGGAGGGGCUGAAAGUAGAAGUGGCUCCCCUGAAGUCUAGUUAGCAUGUUGUGGGAGAGUCCACAUGAAGGGCUGUGGGCUGUAACUCUCUAGUGCACAGUCCUCUCUUUUUGGCGAUGAAAAUUGUAGGGAAAGAAGCGGACAUGCAUGCUGAUUUCACGAGCUGUCUUCAGGAUCUCAGCAGCCUUGCUGUGCUCAAUAUCUUGGAAAUCCACAUCAUUCACAGCUAGAACUUGGUCCCCUUCCUGAAGUCCUGCUCUAUGUGCAUCAGAGUCAGGAAUCACCUUGGAGAUGAAGAUGCCUAGCUGGGAGGCCUUUCCUCCUCAGAUGUUAAAUCCCAACUGAGCUUCAGGAGGCUUCUUCAGUGUGAUGGUUUGGGGCGGAAACUGGGUCAACUCAUUGUUGUAGUCUGGGUGGGGUACCCUCUCAUGAGGAGGAAUCCAUCCUGGAGGAUUCUCAUAGGCAGGCAGGAAAACCACCGGGUAGUCAUCAUAAGGAAUCUGGCUGUCUAUCUCGGGCAAGGCCCAGUGGGCUGUCCCUGACGACCUCAGGCUUCACUCCAUAUUCUAGAUAUUAACACCUUAUGAGAUAGAUUAUUUGCAAAUAUUUUUUCCACUCCAGGUUGCUUUUUUGCUCUGCUGAUUGUAUCCUUUGAUGCACAAAAAUUUUUUAGUUUGAUGCAGUCCCACUUGGCUAAUUUUGCUUUUGGCCGUAUCUAAGAAGUAACUGCCAAGUCCAAAGUAAUGAAGCUUUUUCUUUAUAUUUUCUUCUGGAAGUUUUAUAAUUUAGGUCUUACAUUUAGGUCUUUAGUCCAUUUUGGGUUCAUUUUUAUGUAUAGUAUAAGGGUCCAACUUUUAUUCAUUUGCAUGUGGGUAUCUUAUUUUUUCCAACACCAUUUGUUGAGAAGACUGUCCUUUCCUUAUUGAGUGGUCUUGGCACCCUUGCCAGAAAUCAUUUGACUAUAUAUGUGGGUUUAUUUCUGGGCUGUCUAUUCUAUUCUAUUGGUCUCUUUGUCUGUUUUUAUGCCAUUAUCACACUGUUUUGAUUGGUAAUAUGUUCUGAAAUCGGGAAGUAUAAAUGGCACUUUUAAGUUAUGCUGUUCUAGAUAUUGAAUAAUAAAGAAGUGACAUUAAACAAUUCAAAGAAUUUUUCCUGUUUUUGAAGGAUCGAGACACACUUAGAGAAUGAGGUAAGAUGAUUUUAAUGGCAGAACGUAUGAGGCUACCAAUUGGCAAGGAGCAUAGUAAAAGCUGUGUGUCUAGCACUUCCGGUUUGCAAAGUACUUUCACACAUACAGAGUCCAGUGGCUUGGGAAAGCUUCAAAAAGGCAAUGAAUCUUGAAUUAUCACAACAGUCAGAUGUGUACCUUAGUGGGUAUUCAUACCCAACACUCUGUGUCAGUUGCAUCACAGUGAUUUAGAGAAAUUAUUAUAAGAACUGUCACUUGUGGUAAUUUUUUCCUUGAUGCUGUGUUGUCUUUCCUUUUCCAAGCCAGUAGUUUCAGAUUUCCUGUAUCUGCUUGUUGAAUAGCAGUGGGCCCCAUAUGAAGGUAGAAUACUUAACCACAGCACUGUUUUAUAUUUUGGAUGUGUUAAAAAAUGAAAACAAAAACAAAAACAAAAAAACAGAAAACUGAUCUGGCUGGGUUGUACAGGAUGAAUUGAAGGCAAAAGAUUGAAGCCAGAACAGCAAAUUUAGUGGCUGCUAUAGGAACAAAUUUCGGCUACUUAAGAAAUAUUUUCUCAUCAUCUUAAUACAAUGAUGGGGAUAAUUUUGGUUGAGUAUAUUAUUUGAAGGGACAUUUGGUAGAAUUUCCAUGGAGGAAUAAUGUAGUAUGCUUGUAUGUAGUAGGCCUACCAUAAAGAUUUGUUUAUUAGUGACCAAAUGAAUUUGUAUCUGCAAGGUAUUUGAAUGGUGACCAUAUGAAUUUUUGUUUGCAUAGGUGGGUCUCUAAGGAGUAAUUUAUUCACUUUUCCUGUAAGUGUUUAUUGAAUCCCAUUAUAUGCCAGGGACUGGUGGCUGCUGCUGGUAAACAGGAUACAUGGUUCCUGUCCUUGUAUAGCUGAUACUCUUCUAGUGACUUAUGUGGCCCUUGUCAAUGUUCUGUUCCUCUCCUCUAGUUGGAUUUUUCUUUUAGUCAAAGGCCACCUGUUUUGGUGCAAAAACAAUUGCAGUUGUUUAUGGUCCUAUAUUAAAUAUUAUUUAUAUAUAUAGAGAGAAAUAAACAGUCAACUGCAUUUUGGUUUCCAAGGAGAUAUAUCUUGGCAAAAUUUAUUUUAUCAAGUGCUUUUCUAAGAAAGAGUACCAAAGGAAACUGGCUGUAAUGCCUUUUGGUUAAGAUUUUCCUGAGGACCCAGAUAGGGUUUUUAAAUCUUGGUUUCUUCUACUCCCACACCCACCCCAAAAGAAUCUGGAAAGCUAGUUAUGACUAGUCCUGGGUUUGAUAUUGAUUGCUGGAGCUUUGAAGAGUCAUAUAACCCUUCUGCAUCUUCAUUCAUUCAUUCAUUUCUUCAUUCACUUAAUAAGUCUUCAUUGUUUACCUGUUAUGUAUCAAAUAAUCCUUGUAAAAGGGAGAAAAUUGAGGGUUGAAUUCAGUUUUCUUUAAGACCUACUGUAAAAAUUCUAUAAAUUUAUUACUAUGAUUUAGUAAGAUUUAGGCCUUUUUAUAGAUAGUAGAAAUAUUUUUGAAAGAACUGAAGAAAGAAAUUUAGAGUAUUUGUUUUUAACUCUAAAAUAUUUUAGUGAGAAAAUUCUAUAAUGGUGGAUAAUUUUAGUGUUAGUUCAUUCUGAGCUGAAACCAAUCAACAUUUAAACUCAGCUCAGAGUUUUUCUUUUUAAUUUUGGUAGUAGACAGUUCUGAAUCUAACCUUUCUGUUGUUACAGGUAGCACCCUGGAAACUUAAUGCCUGUUUCAGAUGAUUGGUAUAAUGUGUGUGUAGGAGAUUUGGAAAUGCUUGUUACCUCUUCUAGGUGCUUGGUUCUGAAUCUUUUAGACUAUGGUCAUCUUUUAUGUGUAGUCGUCUUGGGAUAAUGGUAACAUCAUGUCACUGAAUGCAGAACAGUCACACUGAAGAUCUGAGUGCCAUUACUGUGAUAAUUAAGCAGGUAUUUGCUCAUGCUGCCAAAAAAGUAAUAUUCAGAGUUCCUAGUGUGAGAUUUCAUGGCUUUAUAAAGUGAUAUUUUCAUUUUAACUUGUUGGAAAUUCAACAUAGUAUUGACUAUACAUGAAAAGAUUCAGUUAUGCAAAGUAAAAUGUAAGAAUUUCCUCCCAUGUCGAUUGUUGCUUUUCGUAAAUCUGGUUUCAGUGUUACCAAAGAACAGUGGAAGAUUUGUUCUAGUCCUGGCUUUACUACAUACUAGUUGUGUGACUUUGGCUGUCUUUCAUUUACUAAUCAGCAGUAUCAUUAUGCAUUUUGUAGGUGGCAGAUACGUUCUCAUCCUAGGGAUACAUCAAUAAACAACUCUGAGUGAGAUGGGAAGCCACUGGAGGGUUUUGUACAAAGGGUUUUGGUCUGACAUCUUUAAAGAGUGACACUCUGUUGUGUAGGGGAAUAGAAUGGGGAGGAGUGCAAAGGUGGAAAUAGGGGGAUGUUAGAGGUUUCUAGCAAUGCUCUAUAGGUGAGAUAUGAUAGCAGCUGUGGAGGUGAUGAGAAGUGAGUGGUUUCUGGAUAUAUCUCAAAUGGGGCUAAAAUGAUUCACUGGUGGGUGAGAUGAUGUGGAGUGUGACAAAGAGUAUACUCAAGGAUGACACCGAGGUGUUUAGCCUGAGCAGCUGGAAUAAUGGGGAUGCCAUUUAUUGAAAUGGAGAUGCCUAGAGGAGCAAGUUUGGGUGUGGUAUUAAGAGUUGAUCUGUGCAUGUUGGGUAUGAGAUGCAAGUUGACUUGCCAAGUGGAGCAGUCAGGUAGGCAGCUGGGCAGGUCUGUCAGUCUUCAUGAGCUUUAGUUUUCUCAUCUGUGAAAUGGGGAGAGUGUCUGCCCUUCUCAGAAUUCUUGAGAUCAAAUGAGAAAAAAAAAGUUAAAACUUGUAAAGCUGUGUCUUACAUUAUUUCUGGAAAGUAGACUGGCUACCAUCUUGUGUCCUUUGUGGUCUCCUUUGCACUAUUUAACUCAUAGGCCACAUUGUAUUGUGGAAAGUUAGCAUAUGCCCUCCAAAGCCUGGUUUCUUUCCCAGUAGAUGUGAAAGCUUUCUCUUUGAUCCCUCCUGCAAUUCCUGGGCAGCUUCUGGGAGAACUUGGUAUGUAUGUAUUUCAGUUAUCUCCAGGGUGUCAGAGGGCUUCAUUUUGUGUAGAACCAUACUUGAGAGUGUGGUACCAGACUUGCCUCUUAAUAAACAUAGCUUUGGGCCAAAGUAAUUUAUUUAGGUGGGAGGGUAUUGUAGUAGAAAAAUGGCUCUUAUCUUUCUCAAAUUCUUUAUUUUAGGCUUUUUCCAUAACUUGAAUCCAUUAACAGAUAGGGUCUAAUAGGUCAGAUGAUUUUGGGAGACCGCUCUUCAUGUUUCUUGAUUCAGAAAACUUAUAUAUUCUAGUUUUUUUGACUGCUUUACUUUUUUUCAGGCAGGUGAAAUACAUUAAGUAUGUAUUUGAAUCUAUUGAAUUAAAAUUUGCUUAGGAUCCACCAUGUUGAAAGCAUCAGUCUUGUAUUUUUAUCAGUGUCAUUUUGAAUUUAUUAAAUGUCUGUCAUUAGAGGUAGUAGUAAAUAGUUAUAUAUUUGAAAUGUAGUACUUUUAUAAUCUAUACUUUCCUACCAGUUGAUUGUUCCUUUAAGAAUGUCUUGGCUGGGCGUGGUGGCUCACGCCUGUAAUCCCAAGCGCUUUGGGAGGCUGAGGCGGGCGGAUCACGAGCUCAGGAGAUCAAGACCAUCCUGGCUAGCACGGAGAAACCCCGUCUCUACCAAAAAUACAAAAAAUUAGCCGGGCGUGGUAGUGGGCGCCUGUAGUUCCAGCUACUUGGCAGGCUGAGGUAGGAGAAUGGAGUGUGAACCCAGGAGGCGGAGCUUGCAGUGAGCCAAGAUCGUGCCACUGCACUCUACCCUGGGCGACAGAGUGAGACUGUGUCUCAAAAGAAAAAAAAAUGUCUUUAGCCAACAGAUGUGGUGGUUUUGGGUUCUUCUAAUCCACAAGCAGUUUUGAACAGAAACACUAUCACUCUUCACUGCUGUCCUCGUUUGAUUAUCAGUCAGCAAGGUUCCACUGGGCAUCAGCAGUGUGCGCCCAUUGCAGGUCCUCUGAUUUAGAAAGGUCCUGACACAUGCAGUGAAUAUAACUUGAUGACUGCCAUCUAAGUAAGUAUGGUAACCGUUGGAAUACCAUCUAAGUAAGCAUUCUAAGUGUUCAGUGGAAAGAGAAUGGUAAUCGCUUUAAUAAUGAAGGCCUCAGGGAGGUAGGAACCAUGUUUUUCAGGAGAUAUCAUGGGGGCAGAAGUUAUUUUGGAUAGUUUUCUUAUAUGUUUUGAGCAAAAGGACCUCUCUCUACAUGAGGGUUUUUGUUAGGUCUUCAGAUUUAUAAAAUAGGUUUACCCAUCCGCUUAAUAAUUGUUAAGUUACAUAGUCUUUUGCUUUUCAUUGAAUUGGCUUACUGUACAUUAUUUUGUUUCAGCCUCUAAGAAACUGAACCAUAGGUACCCAGUAUAUUACUUGACAUAAUUGUUCAUAAUUGUUGAAGAGAAACCUCAAACCUUGUCUUUCCUUUUUAAGUACAUAUUAGAAAAUUUUGGUCAAUUGUAACAACUAAUUUAAAGGGGAUCUAUAUGUUUAAAUCUGUAUCUUUUUCAUGCUUAAUUUUUCCCCCUAGAAGGAACAUGACUGUCUUAGUCUUCCUAAAGUAUCUUUUAGGCUUUCCAAAUUGUCUGAUGGCUAUUUAUUUGAACUUAAGUGCAAUAGUUGCUUUUAUUGGAGAGAUGCUGAGCGUCUGAGGUUGCAGUAAUUAUUUAUGUACUCCUAAAGUUUUUUUAAAUAACAACUUUAUUGAGUUAUAAUUCUCUAUUUAAAUUAAAAAGUCAGUAGUUCUUAGUAUAUUCAUACAGUUCUGCAGCUAUCUCUAUAAACAAUUUUAGAACAUUUUCAUUACCCCGCAAAGAAACUCCAAGCCCAUUUGCAGUCACCCCCCAUUUCUUUCCAGCCGCACCCCUCCUCUCCGACCCUAGCCCUAGGCUACCACUAACCUACUUUCUGUCUUUAUAGAUUUGCCUCUUCUAUGUGUUUCAUAUAAAUGGGAUCAUACAAUAUUUUGUGUUUUGUGACUGGCUUCUUUCACCUAGCUCUGUCAAAGCACAUUUUUUGCAAGCGCUUUAACUUUGGUGGUAAUGUUACAGAUUUAAGGAUUCAAAACCAAAUAUUCCCUGUCUGCUGACACAGAAACUACAACCUGUGCUGGGACCAGAGAAAAUAGCAAAACGACCAGUUACUAAGUGUGUUUGUAGAACAGGGAGUGAACUUUGAAGCUUUCAUAAAAUAAAACCACCCUAGUACUAAUCCACCAGUGCAUUCAGUACAUGUGAUUGCGUAAUUGUUUUACCGCACCUUUCCAGAGUAUUAUCCUGUUUUUCCCUCGAAUUUCUUGCAGCUCUUAGAAGUCGUUUCUGAUUCUUCCCUUUCUUUUACUUUUGCUCUGAUCUGUGACCAAGCUUUAUCAUUUUUUUCCCUUUGAAUUGAUUUUUUUAGCUUUUGCUCUUAGUUUUAUUGUCACUGUCUUAGAGUGGACCUUGACCCCUGUAUCUAAGCGGCUGUAUCUAGGCUUAGGCCUCCUUUCUGACCCGUUUGACUCCCGCUGUCCCAUUCUCCAGGCCAUCUUGUCUGAUCAUUCUUUCUAAGGGACCACUUAGUUACAUGUGCCACCCUGGAGGAACUCAAGUGGCUCUAAUACUUUGCUACAUCAAAGUCAUACUUUCCUGCUUGCUUUUACGACAUUCCUAUUUGGUCUCUCCAUUUUUGGCCUCUACCAGACUAUGUCUCUGCCUUCCUAUGCUAGGACUUUGCUCUGUCCUCUUCCGUCCUAUUCUGAUUUUCGAAAAAUCUUCAGUUCGUUUUCAGUUUUAGUUAUAUUUAAUUCAAAAAGUAUGGAGGCCAGGUGCGGUGGUUCACACUUGUAAUCUCAGCACUUUGGGAGGCUGUAUCAGUCUCUUCUCACACUGCUAAUAAAGACAUACUUGAGACUGGGUAAUUUAUAAAGGAAAGAGGCUUAAUGGACUCACAGUUCCACAUGGCUGGGGAAGCCUCACAAUCAUGGCAGAAGGCAGAUGAGUAGCAAAGUUACGUCUUACAUGGCAGCAGGCAAGAGAGCAUGUCCUGGAGAACUCCUCUUUAUAAAACCAUCAGAUCUCAUGAGACUUAUUCACUAUCACAAGAACAGCAUGGAAAAGACCAGCAUCCAUGAUUCAAUUAUCUCCCACCGGCUCCCUCCCAUGACACGUGGGAAUUAUGGGAGCUACAAUUCAAGAUGAGAUUUGGGUGGGGACACAGCCAAACCGUAUCAGAGGCUGAGAUGGAUGGUUCACUUGAGCCUAGGAGUUGGAGACCAGCCUGGGCAACAUGGUGAAAUCCUGUCUCUACAAAAAAUAAGCUAGGCAUGGUGAUGCAUGCCUGUAGUCCCAGCUGUUCAGGAGGCUGAGAUGGGAGGAUCGCAUGAGGCCAGGAGGUCGAGGCUGCAGUGAGCAGAGAUAGUGCCACUGCACUCCAGCCUGGGCAGCAGAGUGAGACCAUGUCUUAAAAAAAGAAAAAUGUAUGUGAAAUCUACUAAUUUCCUCAUUUGUUGCUUUAUCACUCUUAUACCCUUCCCUGCAUAUGGUACUCCUUAUCAGUAUCUUGUCUCCCUUUUCCCUCUGGGCACCAGCCCCUGAACACUAGUUUUAUCCCUGUCUUUCUCAUCCUUCAAGACCCACCUUCUUCAUUGAUGUCUUGCUGGUUACCAUAACACACCCUGAUUUCUCCCUUCUCUGACAUGUUGUUGUAUUGUGUUGCGCACUUAAAGAGCCUAGCACUUAAUGAUUAAUGCAUAGUUCAUCAAGGGUGUUUAGCCUGGAGAAAACUCAGAGGGGCAUCAUCCUUUGUCGCAGGAGUCAAAAGUCCAUCAAGUGGAAGGAGGAGAGGUUACCUUUUGUCUUCUCAGGCCUCACAGGACAGAACCAAUGAGUAGAGUAAAUACAGAUAUUUGAGUAAACAUUAGAAAGGACUUUGCUGGUCCAGGUGCUUGCAGUUGUGAUAGGCUGUGUCCCAUCGUUGGAGGCCCUAAUGCAUAAGGCUGGAUCAUUUCUGGACAGGGUCAUUGUAAAGGGCGUUCACAUGAUUCACAUGGGCUCAGUUACACUAGUGAUUAUCUGUCUCGAGUGUCACAGUCAUCCGGGGGCAUUUAAAUACACAGAUUCUCAGCCUCCACCUUGAGAGUUUAGGUUGAGCAGUCUGUGAAGCCAGGCUUGGAAAGUUUUGAAUUAGGUGGCUCUUUUAGUCCUGAGAUCCUAUGAGGCUCAUUUGGUUACUAGAUUUUUAUUUAUUUUAUUUUUAUUUAUUAUUAUUAUUUUUUGAGACAGAGUCUCACUUUGUUGCCUAGGCUGGAGUGCAAUGGUGUGAUCUCGGCUCACUGCAACCUCCGCCUCCUGGGUUCAAGCAAUUCUCCUUCCUCAGCUUCCCGAGUAGCUAGGAUUACAGGUGUGCACCACCACACCCGGCUUCUUUUUGUAUUUUUAGCAGAGAUGGCGUUUCACCAUGUUGGCCAGGCUGGUCUUGAACUCCCAACCUCAAGUGAUCUGCCUGCCUUGGCCUCCCAAAGUGCUGGGAUUACAGGUGUGAGCCACUGUGCAUGGCCAGAUUACCAGAUAUUUAUUGAGUGCCUGUAUUAUAUGGCAAUAUAAAGUUUUUGGUUUUUGCCUUCAUGGAGCAUAGAGUCAAGGGAGUAAUGCAGACAGAGAGCUGAAACCAUGUGAUUUCUCCUCAGGUAGGUAUAGAUUCUCUGAGGAUAGAGACCAUUUCUCUUUUUUUCAUGGUUCUUUAUUUGCCCCAGAGGAAUGGGCACUUUGGGAUUCCUUCUUGACUGGCAAGAUGAUUAACCCGAUGUUUACUGACAAGCCCUCCUUGUGGUAGGGCUUAGUACUAUGUUCUUUAUCUAAGUGUUUUCUUUACUUUUCUUUCUUUCUUUUUUUUUUUUUUGGGACAAAGUCUCGCUCUGUAGGCCAGGCUGGAGUGCAGUGGCAUGAUCUCGGCUCACCGCAACCUCCGCCUCCUGGGUUCAAGUGAUUCUCCUGCCUCAGCCUCCCGAGUAGCUGGGAUUACAGGCACUCACCACUUCACCCGGCUAAUUUUUUGUAUUUUUAGUAGAGACAGGGUUUCACCAUGUUGGCCAGGCUGGUCUUAAACUCCGGACCUCAGGUAAUCCGCCUGCCUCAGCCUGUAAAAGUGCUGGGAUUAUAGGCGUGAGCCACCGUGCCAGGCCUAUCCAAGUGUUUUCAUACAACUUAAUGUCUUGGUUGAGAAGGAGCCACUCUAUCUUCAUUUGUUUCAUGGCAGGUUCUGGCUUUAGAUUUUGUUGCUUCCUGGUAAUUAAUGUCAGCUAUCAUUUAUUGAGUAACCACUGUGUCAGGCACUUUGUGUCACAUUAUUGCUAAUCUUUAUAAACAAGCCUGUGAGAUAGACAUUAGGACUCUGUGGGAGCCAGGAUAUUGAGUUCCUGUUACAGAAUUUCUGCUUCUCUUAACAUAGAUUGUAGCAGCUACUGAGUUGAGGCGUUAUCUAAUGCAGUCAUCUGUUGGGACCAGAGUAAUUGCAGUCAUAUUUUGGCUGUGUGCAUAAAGCAUAUUUUGUUGGGAAUGCCAGAAAGCCUGUCUGCUUAUAAUAGGUAGCUAUGACCACCACCCUGUUAAACUUAUAAUUCGUUUUAAACACUAUGCUGUACUGAUAAUAAAAGAUUUUCAUCUGUUUCUCCAAUGAAAGGCUGAUCUUGCUACUAUAGUUUUAAGCAUGGUAUAUGGUUUAUUAUUCAUUCAUGUUGUGCCCAAAUGGAAAGUCAGGGACUGUUUUUUUUUUCGUAUCUUUAACAAUGAUCUGGAUUUCACAGAGUUGGUGUGUGACCCAUUUGGUGGUUUCUUUUUCUUAUCUGUUGUAGGACUUUGGCCUGUCACGGUGUCGGCCCUAGUGCCCAGUUAGUAAUGACCAUAAAUAUCUUUUGCUGAACAACACCAGUGAAUUCAUUCUGUGUUAGGUUCUUUACUUAUUCCAUCUCAUUUUAUCCUCAUGAAAUUCCUGAAAAAUAGGUAUUAUCAACAUUUAACAGAUGUAAGGAAACUGAGAAAGGCUAAAUAACUUGUCUAGCUUUCAGUUGCUUCCCUAGCUUUCCGAUGCUCCCCUAGUUUUCCGAUGCUCCCCUAACUUUCUGAUGCUCUCCUGUUUACCUGAGGAGACUCAGGCGUGGUUUGCAUAAGAGUUAAUACCAUUUCUUUUUCUUUCCCUCAUUUCUUCCUAUUGUAGGCUUUACUGAGAAAAAUUUGAUGUUACCUGAGGUCAGGAGUUACCAUCCUGGCCAACGUGGCGAAACCCCAUCUCUACUAAAAAAAUACAAAAAAUUAGCCAGGCAUGGUGGUGCAUGCCUGUAGUCCCAGCUUUUCAGGAGGCUGAGGCAGGAGACUUGCUUGAACCCGGGAGGCAGAGGCUGCAGUGAGCUGUGGUUGCACCACUGCACUCCAGCCUGGACAACAGAGCGAGACUCCGUCUCAAAAAAAGAAAUAAAAGUUAAGUGGUAUAUAAGUGAACUUUCAGGAGGUGAAGAUGUACUAGUAUCUCUGACACCUAGAGAAAAGUCAUGGAUAGUGUAUUUAAAGUAGUGCUUGUCAUUGAAUGUCCUUUCUGGCCAACAGAACUUACUGAGAUGUGGGGAGCAACUUCCACAGUGGGCUGACACCUGCCGAGGGAAGUCCAAGGCCCGGGAUUGCAGAUGCUUUUAAUAUGAAUAGCUAGGUGAAAUGUGAAUAUAUAUAGUUAGGUGAAAUAAAUGUAAAUCUUCACUAAGUUUGUAAUAACCACAGAGUUUUUUCUAGUAAGAACAUCUUCACGUUACUUCCCAACUUGAGCAAGACAGGAAGCUUGAGACAUUUAUUUUUUGGGGUGAAAUGCUUUCUUUUUCAUCUUGCAGCAUGGAUUGUGCAAUUGUCAUCUUGUCCUUGACUUCUGCCUAUUGCCCUAAAAUUAUCGGGCUGUCAUCAAGUCAGCAUCUGCUUUGUUUUGAAAUACAUGUCUUUUAAGAGGCUGGAGGCAUAUUAGAAAUAUACAGAUUUUUUUCUCCCCAACUUUUGUUUUAGAUUCAGUGGUACAGGUGCAGGUUUGUUACGUGGGUAUGUUGUGUGAUGCUGAGGUUUGGGCUUCUAAUAAUCUCGUUAUGCAGGUACUGAGCAUCGUACCCAACAGUUAGUUUUUCAACUCAUCCCUCCCUCUCUCUCUCCCCUCUCUAGUAGUUCCAGUGUCUAUUAUUGCCAUUCUUAUGUCCGUGAGUACCCAGCGUUUAGCUCCCAAUUAUAAGUGAGAACAUGUGGUAUUUGCUUUUUCUUUUCCUGCUUUAAUUUGCUUAGAAUAACGGCCUCCAGCUGUAUCCAUGUUGAUGCACAGGACAUGAUUUUACUCUUUUUUUGUGGCUGCAUAGUGUUCUGUGGUGUAUAUGUACCAUAUUUUCUUUAUCCAACCCACUGUUGAUGAACACCUCCUUUGAUUCCAUGUCUUUGCUGUUGUGAAUAGUGUUGUGAGGAACGUGUGAGUGUAUGUGUCUUUUCAGUAGAAUGACUUGCUCUUCUCUUCUUUUUUUUUGGAGACAGGGUCUCACUUUGUUGCCCAGGCUGGAGUGCAGUGGUAUCAUCUCUGCUUACUGCAACCUCUGCCUCCUGGGUUAAAGUGAUUCUCCCAUUUCAGCCUCCCGAGUAGCUAGAACUGUUGUUGUGCCCCACCAUACCUGGCUAAUUUUUAUAUUUUUUGUAGAGAUGGGGUUUUGCCUUGUUGCCCAGGCUGGUCUCAAAUUCCUGGAUUCAAAUGAUCCACCUGCAUUUUUGGGGGCCAUUUUUUGUCCCCCAAAGUGCUGGGAUUAGAGAUGUGAGCCACCGUACCUGGCCUGUUUUCCUUUGGGUAUAUACCUAGUAGUGGGAUUGCUGGGUUGAAUGUAGCUCUGUUUUAAGCUCUUUGAGAAAUCUCCAAACUGCUUUCCACAGUGGCUGAACUAAUAUACAUUCCCACCAACAGUGUAUAAGAGUCCCCUAGAAAUAUACAGAUUUUUAAAGAGAUGUUGAUGGAAGUGAAGUUAAUUGAAAAUACCGAAAAUACAAGUGUAAGUUCAGUCUUGGCUUUUCCAAGUAUUCAUCUAGGAAGCAUGUUCAGUUGAUCAGACAGAAAUGAAAUUGCUGGUAAAGUUCUUGUAGUUAACUUAGAUUAUGAUGGGAAAGGAGUACUUUUUUUAUACCUGAACUUUUCUAUUGAGUUUUGGACUGUGUAUGUUUUUUGAAUCCAGUAUACCCACUUUAAACCUUACGUACAGCUCAUUUCUCCAAACCAAAUAUUUGAGAUUUCUCUUUCAUGUUUAUAAAUCCUCAAGAUUUUUGCUUUGGUUUAUUAGAUAAGGAUUUUUGGUGGUAUAAUAACUAGGUUGGGUGGUUUUAUCUUAAUCUCUCGUUUGCUUUAAUAUUUAGUUUUAUUUAAUCUCCUAAGAACGAAGAUUAAUUUUAAAAAGGAUUGUUAAACUUUCGUGGCCAAAGAAGGCCACGAUGUGCCUUCUAAAUGGCAGAGAGCUCCAAAAUUAUUUAAUGAAUUCCACUCCUGGUGCACUCAUUUAUAGCAAGAUGUGCAAGGACCUUAGCCUAUUUAUCAUCCUGUUCUUGGUUUACCAUUGCAACAAUAAAUCACCUUGAUUGGUUCACCUUGACUUCACGUUACAGACUUUUCAUGUUGACCUGCUUAAGAGUGUUUGAAAGCUACCUUUUAAAUAAUGUCCUAUAACCACAAUAAUCCAACAGUAUUGAGGACAUGCCACCCUCAAACCUUGGUCCACCCACCAUCAAUCCACAAAGUCCGUUUCUAAAUAUUACCUAAUAUUCAUCAUCCACUCAGCAAAUACUUUUUGAGCUGUUUCAUGUCAGGCGCUGGCUGUGGAUGAGCUAUGUAUUUCGUAGAUAACACUGCAGUUCUGUUCUCAGGAUGCUUCCAGCUAGUUGGGAAUUCAGGAAGAAUAGAGAAAAAUAUCUUAUCAGGAGAUGAAGGAAAUAAUUUAAAUGUACCGUCUUUGAUAUUUUCCUCUUUGUAUUAUGGAAGCAGUAUAUAAGACUUCGUGGAAAAUUUGGAAAAUACAGGAAAGUAUGAGGAAGAAAAAUGUCAUCCAUCAUUCUGCCACCCAAGAAUAACCACUGUUACUACUUUCAUGUUUCUUGUCUUUAAAAAAUGGCUUCUAAAAACAAGCAGAACAGAGCUCUGUCCAGUAAAAGGCUUUAAGGUGAAAUUUGAUGAGGGAAAGGAAAAAAAGGCCCCCAGAAAUGUUUCUGCUGUUGUGGGGGACCAUGCUGUGGAAGCAGCAUCUUGGGGAAGGGAUGUCUGGGAGUUCUCAGGAAGAAAGUAUCAGGGAACAAAACCAAGAACAGUGUUUACCUUAGAUUUCCAAGUUACAAGUGUGUUGUGUUCUAAAACUUGAUGAGGUGGUAAUUGGCAUUCCAGAUGCUUUUCUCAGAUACUAAUCUAUGCUAGAUGAGUAAAUGGAGUCUUCCCUCUAGGACAGAAUAUGCGAGAUGAUUUUUAGAUUGCAGUGUCCACUGCGUGUCCACGGUUUAAGGUUUGGAGAAUUUAUAAUAGGAGAAGCAAGGAAAAAACAUUUUUUUUGAAGGGUCUCUUAGGUACUAGCACUUUUUUUGAAGUCAGUGUUUCAUUUAAUGUUCAUAGCAAACAUUUGAAGGAAGUAUUUCCCUCAUUUUUGUAGUUCAGAUUUAGGAAUUGGAUUUAAUUGCUUGUUUACAGUCAUAGUGUUUCAUAUUAAGUGGUAGGGGCACAUGCAGGCUUUGGAACCAGAGACCUGGGUUCCGCCCUACCACAGUGAUCUCAGACAAUUCCUCAACCUCUUUCUUAAUUUUUAAAAGGAAAAGAUGAUGAUGCUUAACUCAAGGUUAUUAUAAAGAUGAAAUGAGACAAUGUAUAUAGCACCCUUCCCACAGUUUAGAUUUAGGAUCAAUGAGUGAGAGCUUUUAGUAUGUCACUUGUAAGGCAGCAGGCCCAGUGCCUGACAUAUAGUAGAUGUCCAAUAGAUGUUGGACCCAGGGCUUCUUACAAGCCCUCCCAACUUUUCAGGUUUUUAAAAAUUUCUCUAUCUGUCUGUCUGUCUGUCUGUCUAUCGAGAGAGAUGGGGUCUCAGUCUGUUGCCCAGGCUGGAAUGCUGUGGUGUAAUCUUGGCUCACUGCAACCGCUGCCUCCUGGGCUCAAGUGAUCCUCUCACUUCAGCUUCCUGAGUUGCUGGGACUGUAGGUGUGCGCCACUAUGCCCAGCUAAUUUUUUGUAUUUUUUGGUAGAGACGGACGGGGUUUUGCCACGUUACACAGGCUGCUCUCCAACUGCUGAGCUCAAGUGAUCCGCCAGCUUCAGUCUCCCAAACUGCUAGGAGGUGUCGUGAGCCACUGUGCCUGGCAUGCCAACUUUUCAAUUUUUUCUAGUGUCUUUCUCUUGGAUUUUGAAGGACCUUAAUGGAAAGAUAUAUUUCAUUUGAAUUAUCAUGGUGGAUUCUUGGAUUUGUAAAAUAAAUGUCAUCUGCACUGCACAGGAAAAUUCCAUCUCAUCAGUAGUUUUCUUUGAAAGGUCAUCCUGAACAUUUUCCCCUGGGUGUCUGGGGAAGGCUAAGGGUAGGAAGGCUAAGAGCCCAGGUGGGAGUGGGGGAGAAGGAGAGCAGGAGGAGUCAAUUUGGGUAUUUUCCUGGCGUAGUUUGCUACCUACCCACCUUAGUAAGGACUGUACUAUGGCCAUGUGUGACUGGGAUUGUAAUGGAGCAGAGGUUAAGAGGGCACUGUGUGGGAGACGGGUACUAUGUGGAAGAUAUUUGGUUCUCCGUGCAUACUCAUGCUCUUUCAUGCACUUAUUCAGUCAUCAGACAGUUGUUGACGCUUUCCUAUAUGCAGUGCACUGUGCCAGUCCUUUGGGAUUCAAAGGAUGUCCUCACCUCUGUAGGAUUAAGCCAAGUUGAUAGACAAGUAACAGAAAGUUACAGCUCAGUUUUAAGUGCCAAGUUAGAGGGAAGCUGGGGGAGCUUUGCCAAAGCAUAUUAAAAUUAUUUUUCUGUAUUUGCUUCAUUAGACCUUGAAGGCCAGGACUAUGUCUUUGCAACUUGAUUUUUCCCACAGCUUACUCUUUUUUUUUUUUUUUUGAGAUGGAGUCUCGCUCUGUCGCCCAGGCUGGAGUGCAGUGGCGCGAUCUUGGCUCACUGCAAGCUCUGCCUCCCGAGUUCAUGCCAUUCUCUUGACUCCUGAGUGGCUGGGACUACAGGCGCCCGCCAUCACUCCCGGCUAAUUUUUUUGUAUUUUUAGUAGAGACGGGGUUUCACCGUGUUAGCCAGGAUGGUCUCCACCUCCUGACCUCGUGAUCCGCCUGCCUCGGCCUCCUAAAGUGUUGGGAUUACAGGCGUGAGCCACUGCGCCUGGCACCCAGAGCUUACUCUUAUAUGCAUCCCUGAAUAAAUUUGUAUAAUUUAUUAUUAUUAUUUUUUGAGAUGGAGUCUCUGUUGCCAGGCUGGAGUGCAGUGGCACGAUCUUCGCUCACUGCAGCCUCCGCUUCCCGGAUUCAAGCAAUUCUCCUGUCUCAGCCUCCCGAGUAGCUGGGACUACAUGCGCUUGCCACCACGCCCAGCUAAUUUUUGUAUUCUUAGUAGAGAUGGGGUUUCACCAUGUUGGCCAGGAUGGACUUGAUCUCUUGACCUCAUGAUCUGCCUGCCUCGGCUUCCCAAAGUGCUGGGAUUAUAGGUGUGAGCCACCGCACCCAGUCAAAUUUGUAUAAUUUUUAACCUGACACAGAGACAAGGUAGUUUAUAAAUGGUGUGUUUAAACUAUAUGUGUGGAAAUCUCAACCCUGUAACUGGAGACAUCUGAUAAGUCUUAGACUUACUGAUAAUUUCAUUUUUAGAAGGUAGAGGUGGAAAUUUGACUAGUUAAUUCAUGCUGAGAACUUUGGGUGAAACUGGCUAUUUUAUUCUGGGGUUUCAUCCUGAUGGAAGUUGUGCAAGACCCUCUUGCACAUGAGAUUUUUAGAAAGGUGUCUCAUGAAGCUCAGAGCAAAGAUGGUAUUACCUCCAAGGCCAGCAGAACUGUAGAAGAGAGUAUGGUUUCAUCGAGAUGUGUGGGGAGCGCCAAGAAACAAAAAUUGUGAUUGUAUGAUUGCAAGUCAUGAUGGUAAGCAAAAGCGGGGAUGGCUUCUAAAGAAGUCAACAAAGUGUUCAGGGUCAUUGGAAAAGAAGCCAGAUUUUAAAAAAGAUUAUUGAGAUAUAAUUCACACAUUAUACAGUUAGCCCAUUUAAAGUGUACAAUUUAGUGGCUUUUAAUGUAUUCACAGCUGUGUGUAACCAUCACAACAAUUUUAGAACAUUUUCAUUACCUCAAAAAUAAAUUUCAUGCACGUUAGUUAUCACCCUCCUGCCUAUCUUUCUAUCUCCCUAGCCCUAAGCAACCACUAACCUACUUUCGGUCUCUAUUGAUUUGUCUGUUCUGGAUGUUUCAUGUAAAUUUAAGCAAUAUGUAGUCUUUUUUUUUUUUUUGAGACAGUCUUGCUCUGUUGCCCAGGCUGGAGUGCAGUGGUGUGAUCUCGGCUCACUGCAGCCUCUGCCUUCCAGGUUCAGGCGAUUCUCCUGUCUCAGCCCCCCGAGUAGUUGGGAUUACAGGCACACGCCACUACGUCUGGGUAAUUUUUUUUUUUUUCGUAUUUUUAGUAGAGAUGGGGUAUCACCGCGUUGGCCAGGCUGGUCUUGAACUCCUGACCUCAAGUGAUCCACCUGCCUCGGUCUCCCAAAGUACUGGGGUUACAGACAUGAGCCACCAUGCCCAAACAAAAUGUAGUAUUUUGUGACUGGCUUCUAAUAAUGUUUUCAGGGUUUGUACAUGUUGUAGCAUAUAUCAUACUUUAUUUCUUUGUCUUGUCAAGUAAUAUUCUAUUCUAAUAACAUUUUGUUUUUUUCUGUUCAUCAGUUGAUGGACACUUGGGUUUUUCUACUUUUUGGCUAUUAAGAAUAAUGUUGCUUUGCAGGUGUAAGUUUUAACGUGCACAUAUGUUUCCAUUUUUUCUUGGAUAUAUACCUAGGAGUUGAAUUGUUGACUUAUAUAGUAACUCUAUGCUUAGUAACUCUAAACAAUCCGGGCUUUUGAGGAACUGCCGGACUGUUUUCCAAAGUGGCUGUACCAUUUUCCAUUUCCACGAGCAGUGUAUUAAGGUCCCAGUUUCUCCACAUCUUUGCCAACACUUGUUACUGUAUGGCUUUUCUUUUUAUUUUUGCUGUCAUAAUAGGUGUGAAUGACUUUUAUUUCCUUAAUGACUAAUGAUGGUGAGCAUCUUUUUAUGUGUUUGCUGGCCAUUUGUAGAUCUUUGGAGAAAUGUCUGUUUACAUUUUUUGCCCAUUUUAAAGUUAAGGUUUUUGUCUUUUUUUGUUGAGUUGUAAAUAUUCCUUAUGUAUUUUAGAUACAGAUCUUUUAUUAGAUUUGCAAAAUGUUUCACUCUGUGGGUUGUCUUUCUAUUCAGGAGGCCAGACUUUAAGUGGAAUACAAAAGAGAAAAGGGCAUGUAGUAAGCAUGAAAACAAAAGAAUAGGCCGAACUGCUACAAAUAUUUUAGACAGAGUAUACCUAGGGUGACCUGUGGCUUGCAGGAAAAAAAUUUGAAAUUACCACAGUGAUUUAAAAAAAUUUUUGGAAGUAUAAUCCACAUCAAGUAUGCAAACUGUAAAGGUACAGCUUGAUAAAUGAUCACAAAAUGCAUACACACAUGUAACCACCAUGCAGGGUCAACACAGAGACUAUUACCAGCCCCCACAAAAGCCAUCUUCUGCACCUUUGCAAUCAUUAGCCCUCCUGCACCCCAAAGAUAACAGCUCUUUUGAUUUCUGUCACCAUUGAUUAGUUUUUAUAUAUUUUUUGAAAUUUGUAGAAAUGGGAUUUUACAGCAUGUUUUCUUUUGUACCUGGUUUAUCUUGCCUAACAUGUAAAAUUUAUCCAUGUAUUUCCUGUAGUUCAUUUUCUUUAGUCAAUAGUUUUCCGUUGUAUCAAUAUCCAACUCUUUAUACUGUCUUCUUUUGAUGGAUGUUUGAGUUUCAGUUUUCAACUUCUGGUCAUUAGGCCCUUUCUUGCAUGCAUGUUGAGGUGCACAUGGGGCAUGCCUUCCCAUUAGAUGUAUGUCUAAGAGUGGACUUGCUGUGUCAUAAAGUGUAUCUGUGUUCCGCUUUAUUAAAGUGUAUGCAAAUUAGUUUUUAAGCUUUAAAACAAAGUGAUAACUAAAAAGAGGCUAAACCCACUGUUUAAUUUUAACAAAAGGGAUUUCAGAGUAAUUCACUCCUUUUUCUUAGUAUCUUUUAUGGUAGGAAAGUAUUUUUCAGACAGAGAAGGGUAGAAUAUGAAAGAUGAGAGUAAAGCAAACAAGUUCUUACUCACUUAAAAUAAAUAAGAAUCUCCAGGCUGAAAUGGAUUCUUCCCCAGGAUACUGAAAACUCUACCAUUAAUUUGAGGAACCGCAGUUGGGAAACUUCGAGAACUGAUAAGGUGAGAGAAGCUCUUACAGGGGCAAAAAGAUGAUACCUUUUCCUCAUCCACCGCAAGGGUUGUGGUCAGUACUACUGUUAGCAAAAGACAGGUUAGCAAGAAAGAAAAUAUCACAGAUUUGUUUAACAAAGUUAUAUAUGACGUGGGAGCUUUCAGAAAUGAAGACUCAAAGACCCAAGGAAAACUUUCUAUGCUUACAUUUGAUGGAGAAUCAUGGCCAUGUAGUAAUGUGAUUGCACAAAAAGGGAAUGAUCUAAUGGUAAUAAACUGAGAGGGGAACCCAGCAAGGCCUGUCCAGAUUCUUCUCAGCCUCUCUGUGUUGAGCAUUACUUUUCUGCUGGGUGUGGGGCAGAACCCUUCUGGAAUAAGGGUCUUAUGAUCUAUUUUCAGGUAAGAUGGGUCGGAGAAUUCCUUUAUGACCAUGCUUCACAUAGAAGGCAGGGGAAGUGACCUUGUUUCUGGGCCCCCUCCAGUUUCCUUCAGUUCAGAAUCCUUUGGGGGUAAUGUAUUCUGAGCCCUGACACUCCUGAAAUCUGAAGGUUUACGUCAGUGUUUUCAUUUGUUUUCCCUAAAGAAAGGAAAUAGAUUUUUUUUUCCUAGAGAAAGGAAACUAGAAAAAGUUUCAUGUGACUUUCUGACAGAAUUUUAGUAUAGGUUUAAACAGGUGAUUUGAUAGCAUGAGAGAAAAAGGUAGUGGUUACCAGGAGCCAGGAUGGUUUCAAUAUUACAAAAAACAUUCACUGGGUUUCUAAUUCCUGUGGGUUCCUGGUACUCCUGCUGCCGGAGGAACAAAGGUGAAUGUCAAGUUCUGAAUUUAGGAGGUCAGCUUGUAGCUAGUAUCCUUAGUGCAUUUCCUUGCACAUAUUUUUUGAUGGCCCAAGAGUGGGGGAAGCAGACGCAUUAGUAAGUAAUCCCCAAAUAUAGGCAGAGUGCCUAGGAACCUGGUUAAGGAGUGCUCUUGUGACACUGGGGAGGAUGUGGAGAAUAGGACAUCUUUUGAAGAGGUGAUACUGCUUCUAAAAUCUGAAGAGACUAAGGGAAAAUAGAGUAGGGUGGGGAGGGCAGGCAGGUGCUGAGGCUUGGUUAUAAGAGCAUUUCUGCUAGAUGGAGUAAAGUGAUUAUGAAAAAACUUUUUAGAAGUGGGAGGUCUCGAACUCCUAUUCGUGAUCACAGACCUCGUGAUCUGCCUGCCUUGGCCUCCUAAAGUGCUGGGAUUAUAGGCGUGAGCCACCGCGCCUGGUUAAUGUGGUGAAACCCCGUCUCUACUAAACACACACACACACACACACACACACACACAAUUAGCUGGUCAUGGUGGUAUGUGCCUGUAAUCCCAGCUACUCGGGUGGCUGAGGCAGGAGAAUUGCUUGAACCCAGGAGGUGGAGGUUGUAGUGAGCCGAGAUCGCACCACUGCAUUCCAGCCUGGGCGACAGAGCAAGACUCUUUCUCAAGACAAAACAAAAAAAAGUGGGAGGUAUUGCCACUGAUUGGCCUUACCCGAUUGGCCACUGAUUGCCACCGAUUGGCAAAACCUAGUGAGGUUUUGCCUAUUAUGCUAAGGACUUGGGGCUUUUAUACGCCUAGGGGAGCCCUGGAAAGAUUUUAAAUAUCCAGGGAGCAGAAUGAUCAGAUUUGCAUUGAAAAAGUUUGCUCAUAAUGUGGAAAAUGUACUGAUCUGGGUCCGGGGACAUAGGAAACUCUUACAAGAGUGAAGUUAGGGAUUGCAGUGGUCCUAAGUCCCCCAGAGGGACUUAGGAGAGACUAAAAUAAGUCAUUCUGUGCUAAUCUUGUUUUCCUUUAAAGAUAGAUUCUGAAAAGUUUAAAUAGGUUAUUAGUUAGGGGAAUGCUGUCUUUUGAUUUCAACGGAAUAUUUAGUUUAACAAAAGGCUGUCCUUAUGAACAAGAUGGGAAAAUGUGAUAUGGGUAUUAGGUGGAUUUGUAGCUUGUUGAAUAGUAGAUUUGAUGGAUCUGCACAAGCUGGAAGAGAAGCAUUUUGUCCUGUGCUGUUGCGCUCUGUAUUUGAUUUCUGUGGGUUACAACUUUGAUCUGUGAAAUAGUUUUAUUGUUAACAAAUUUAUAUGUGAAGUUAGAAAGGUAAGGUAGUUGACAAAUUACUUUUCAAGUUUAAAAUAUGCCUUUAUAAAAUUUCAAAGAGGUGAAAUUGGUUGUAGGGGUUGUGGGGGCAGAAAUGCUACUCUUUAGGUUGCAAGUACAGUAUAAUUACAUAAACAGAUAAAUAGUUUUUCUGUGAUACUAAAAUUUCAUGGGAGAGGGUGAUUAAGAAAAAAUGCCUAAAAAGUCUCUUUAGGGGUGCAGUGAUGGAAAAAAGUUGAGAACCACAGGUUUAAAAGAAAGCUGUUGAAAUGGCUAGCCAAAACUUGGAAUACAUGGAGAUAGUUGAAAAUUUCUACAUUUAGGACUCAACACUAAAGGUACCAUGAUAGGUUGGGAAUAUUUCAUGAUUUAUGUUUAUGUGAAGGAAAAAAAUGGAAUUAAAUCCCUUUGUUACUUUUAUUUGCUUCUAAACUCAGUAUGAGUCAGUAGGGUGGAUAUGACUGAGAGAAAGGUUAAUGCAGCCUUAGCUUUCAUUUAUAAAAUUAGGUGUAAAUAGAAUUCAGAGUGUAAGAGUUUCCUGUAUGGUUUCCUAAUACGGUUUAUUAUUACCAUAAACUGAUCAGAACCUGAUCUGGAACUUGGAAGAUGAGAAGUCUCAAAACCAUGUUGAGAAGCGUUAUUCAGACAGAACAACAACCAACUUAUUGUUUAAAUAUAACAAGACAACUGUAAGAAUUUAUGGCUUGAAUCCACAAACAUAAUUAAACAAUUAAAUUGGGCAAUGCUGUAUAAUUAAUAGAUUAAUUAAAUCUAUAUUGAGUGCCUACUAUCUUCCAGGUGUUAUUCUAGCUACUGGGGACUCUGUACUCAGCCAACUGGACAAAAUAUCUGUGUUCAUGGAACUCACAGGUUUUGAGAGAUUACCUGAAGUUGCACUCAAAAGCAAGAUAUACUACUAACUUUGAAAUGGAAUAAGAACAUAAGAGAGCAGCUGCCCAUGCCAAAUAGUUACCUCUUUUAAACUCAUUCUACUGGAGCAAAUGGCCCUCCCUAUCCUGAAGACAUUAGCUGAGAGUCUGGCACCUUUUAAAGGUCUGAUCAUCAAUUGUCUCUCUGGGCGGCCACCUAUGAGACUUCAUCUGUGUGGUUAUACCUUAUUGGUGUGGACGUUGUCUAAAUUUCGGUAGCCAUGGCACAAGAAUAUAGUGGACUUACAGUUUCUGGCUACUACUGGUGGAAAAUGAUGGGCUCAGACAAGAGAAAGCAUGGGAUUAUGGCAACCACAGAAUCUCAGUAGUACAAGUUCCAUUCAGUUUUUUCUGAAAGAAAGCCCUCUGUUAAAGUGAAGCAAAGAAACUGUUGUGGAUUAUAACGUUUAGAAGUUCCAAUUUUUCAGUGCUUUACAAAUAAAGCAUCAUUUAACCUUUUAAAUGAAAAAGAUUAAGAUCUCAUGCAACUGUUGUAUUUUCUGGAAGCCAUUCUCCAAAAGGGAAGUGCACAUUUAAAACACAGAUAUGAUGGUCCUUGCUGCAGGGAUUUAAGUCUACUUGCUUUUACAUCAUGACCAGCUUGAAACGGUCACAGACAGAAAGGCCUCUUGCCACUGACAGGGCCUCUGUUGUUGGCACAGACGGCACCCCCAAAGUCCACACUGAUGAUUUCUACAUGCGGCGCUUCCGGUCCCAAAAUGGCAGCUUAGGAUCAUCAGUUAUGGCUCCUGUAGGACCCCCCCGAAGUGAAGGUUCUCACCAUAUAACCUCAACCCCCGGAGUCCCAAAAAUGGGGGUAAGGGCAAGGAUUGCAGAUUGGCCCCCAAGAAAGGAAAACAUAAAAGAAUCUAGCCGUUCAAGCCAGGAAAUAGAAACCUCAAGUUGCCUUGAUAGCCUGUCCUCCAAAAGCAGUCCUGUGAGUCAGGGAAGUUCUGUUAGCCUCAAUUCCAAUGACUCAGCCAUGCUGAAAAGCAUACAGAACACGCUGAAAAACAAGACAAGACCGUCGGAGAACAUGGACUCCAGAUUUCUCAUGCCUGAAGCCUACCCCAGCUCCCCCAGAAAAGCUCUUCGCAGAAUACGCCAGCGAAGCAACAGUGAUAUCACCAUAAGUGAACUUGAUGUGGAUAGCUUUGAUGAAUGUAUCUCACCUACAUACAAGACUGGACCAUCACUGCACAGGGAAUAUGGUAGCACAUCUUCAAUUGAUAAACAGGGAACAUCUGGAGAAAGCUUUUUUGAUUUGUUAAAGGGCUACAAAGAUGACAAAUCUGAUCGAGGUCCAACUCCAACCAAGCUCAGUGACUUUCUCAUUACUGGUGGUGGCAAGGGUUCUGGUUUCUCUUUGGAUGUAAUAGACGGGCCUAUCUCACAGAGAGAGAACCUCAGGCUUUUUAAGGAAAGGGAAAAACCACUCAAGCGACGUUCAAAAUCUGAAACUGGAGACUCAUCUAUUUUUCGUAAAUUGCGCAAUGCCAAAGGUGAAGAACUUGGGAAGUCAUCAGAUCUUGAAGAUAACCGAUCAGAAGACUCUGUCAGGCCCUGGACAUGUCCAAAGUGCUUUGCCCACUAUGAUGUCCAGAGUAUAUUAUUUGAUUUGAAUGAGGCAAUUAUGAACAGGCACAAUGUUAUUAAGAGGAGAAACACCACCACUGGAGCUUCCGCAGCUGCCGUGGCAUCCUUGGUCUCUGGACCUCUGUCUCAUUCAGCCAGUUUUAGCUCCCCAAUGGGCAGCACAGAGGACCUGAAUUCCAAAGGAAGCCUCAGCAUGGACCAGGGAGAUGAUAAAAGCAAUGAGCUUGUAAUGAGCUGUCCAUAUUUUCGGAAUGAGAUAGGUGGAGAAGGGGAGAGGAAAAUCAGCCUUUCAAAAUCAAAUUCUGGCUCCUUUAGUGGAUGUGAAAGUGCCUCCUUUGAGUCUACCCUUAGUUCCCAUUGCACAAAUGCAGGAGUGGCAGUACUUGAAGUGCCCAAGGAGAACUUGGUGUUGCACCUAGAUAGAGUGAAAAGAUACAUCGUGGAACACGUAGAUCUGGGUGCAUACUAUUAUAGAAAAUUUUUCUACCAGAAGGAACACUGGAACUAUUUUGGGGCUGAUGAGAAUCUUGGUCCAGUGGCUGUGAGCAUUCGAAGGGAAAAACCAGAUGAAAUGAAAGAAAAUGGAUCUCCGUACAACUACCGAAUAAUUUUUAGAACUAGUGAGCUCAUGACACUGAGAGGUUCGGUCCUGGAGGACGCCAUUCCGUCGACAGCCAAGCACUCGACAGCCAGAGGCCUGCCUCUCAAAGAAGUGCUGGAGCACGUGGUUCCUGAGCUCAAUGUCCAGUGCCUGCGGUUGGCCUUCAACACACCCAAGGUCACAGAGCAGCUCAUGAAACUGGAUGAACAAGGGCUGAACUACCAGCAGAAAGUAGGCAUCAUGUACUGCAAAGCUGGACAGAGCACUGAAGAAGAGAUGUACAACAAUGAGUCAGCUGGCCCAGCCUUUGAAGAAUUUCUUCAACUAUUGGGAGAGCGAGUUCGGCUCAAAGGAUUUGAGAAGUAUCGAGCACAGCUUGAUACCAAAACUGACUCCACUGGAACCCAUUCUCUGUACACAACAUACAAAGAUUAUGAAAUUAUGUUCCAUGUUUCUACCAUGCUGCCAUACACACCCAACAACAAACAACAGCUCCUGAGGAAGCGGCACAUUGGAAAUGAUAUCGUAACAAUUGUUUUCCAAGAGCCUGGAGCACAGCCAUUCAGCCCAAAAAACAUCCGAUCCCACUUCCAGCACGUUUUCGUCAUCGUCAGGGUGCACAAUCCGUGCUCUGACAGUGUCUGUUAUAGUGUGGCUGUUACCAGGUCCAGAGAUGUGCCUUCCUUUGGGCCUCCCAUUCCUAAAGGGGUCACUUUCCCUAAGUCAAAUGUGUUCAGGGACUUCCUUUUGGCGAAAGUGAUUAAUGCAGAAAAUGCUGCUCAUAAAUCGGAGAAGUUUCGGGCCAUGGCAACUCGGACCCGCCAGGAAUACCUGAAAGAUCUGGCAGAAAAGAAUGUCACCAACACCCCUAUCGACCCUUCUGGCAAGUUUCCGUUCAUCUCUCUGGCUUCCAAGAAGAAGGAAAAGUCUAAGCCAUAUCCAGGAGCCGAGCUCAGCAGCAUGGGGGCCAUUGUAUGGGCAGUCCGGGCUGAAGACUACAACAAGGCCAUGGAACUAGACUGCCUUUUAGGGAUCUCCAAUGAGUUCAUUGUGCUCAUUGAACAGGAAACAAAGAGCGUGGUCUUCAAUUGUUCCUGUAGAGAUGUGAUAGGGUGGACUUCAACUGACACCAGCCUCAAAAUCUUCUAUGAACGAGGAGAAUGUGUUUCAGUGGGUAGUUUUAUUAACAUUGAGGAGAUCAAAGAGAUUGUCAAAAGGUUGCAGUUUGUUUCAAAAGGCUGUGAAUCGGUGGAGAUGACUCUGCGAAGAAAUGGGCUAGGACAGCUUGGCUUCCAUGUCAACUAUGAGGGCAUUGUGGCGGAUGUGGAGCCCUACGGUUAUGCCUGGCAGGCAGGGCUGAGGCAGGGCAGUCGCCUGGUGGAGAUCUGCAAGGUGGCGGUAGCCACUCUGAGCCAUGAGCAGAUGAUCGACCUCCUGAGAACAUCUGUCACGGUGAAGGUUGUCAUCAUUCCCCCGCAUGAUGACUGCACCCCGCGGAGGAGUUGCUCUGAAACCUACCGCAUGCCAGUGAUGGAGUACAAAAUGAAUGAAGGUGUUUCAUACGAAUUCAAGUUUCCCUUCCGAAAUAAUAACAAGUGGCAGAGGAACGCCAGCAAGGGGCCUCAUUCACCUCAAGUCCCGUCCCAGGUGCAGAGUCCCAUGACCUCGCGGCUGAAUGCUGGAAAAGGAGAUGGGAAGAUGCCUCCUCCAGAAAGAGCCGCCAACAUCCCUCGAAGCAUCUCCAGUGACGGGCGCCCACUAGAGAGGCGGCUGUCUCCUGGUUCGGACAUCUAUGUGACGGUCUCAUCCAUGGCUUUAGCAAGAUCCCAGUGUCGGAACUCUCCUAGCAACUUGUCUUCAUCCAGUGAUACUGGUUCUGUGGGGGGCACUUACAGGCAGAAGUCCAUGCCCGAAGGGUUUGGAGUGAGCCGUAGAUCCCCAGCCUCCAUUGACAGGCAGAACACCCAGUCAGAUAUUGGUGGCAGCGGAAAAUCCACGCCUAGCUGGCAAAGAAGUGAGGAUAGCAUUGCUGACCAGAUGGCUUACAGUUAUAGAGGACCUCAGGAUUUCAAUUCUUUUGUCCUCGAGCAGCAUGAAUAUACAGAGCCAACAUGCCAUCUCCCAGCAGUAUCAAAGGUACUGCCAGCUUUCCGAGAGAGCCCCAGUGGGAGAUUAAUGCGGCAGGAUCCAGUGGUUCAUUUGUCUCCAAACAAACAAGGGCAUUCUGAUAGCCACUACUCGAGCCACUCCAGUAGCAAUACUCUCUCCAGCAAUGCGUCAAGUGCCCAUAGUGAUGAGAAGUGGUACGAUGGGGACCGCACAGAAUCCGAACUCAACAGCUAUAACUAUCUGCAAGGCACCUCUGCUGACAGUGGCAUUGACACCACCUCUUAUGGCCCCAGCCACGGCAGCACAGCCUCGCUGGGGGCUGCCACAUCGUCACCUCGCUCAGGGCCAGGCAAGGAGAAAGUGGCACCCCUAUGGCACAGCUCCAGUGAAGUAAUCUCCAUGGCAGAUCGGACUUUGGAGACAGAGAGCCACGGCCUGGACCGGAAAACAGAGUCUUCCCUGAGCUUAGACAUACACAGCAAGAGCCAAGCCGGCUCGACCCCUCUGACAAGGGAGAACAGCACCUUCAGUAUAAACGAUGCUGCUUCCCACACAAGUACCAUGAGCUCCCGACACUCUGCCAGCCCAGUGGUUUUCACCAGUGCCCGGAGUUCACCUAAAGAAGAGCUUCAUCCAGCUGCCCCCUCACAGCUCGCACCAUCCUUCUCCUCCUCUUCCUCCUCCUCCUCUGGUCCUAGGAGUUUUUACCCUCGCCAGGGCGCUACUAGCAAGUACCUGAUUGGAUGGAAAAAACCCGAAGGAACCAUAAACUCCGUGGGAUUUAUGGACACGAGAAAGCGUCAUCAGAGCGAUGGCAAUGAAAUAGCCCACACCAGGCUGCGUGCCUCAACCAGAGACCUCCGGGCAUCUCCUAAGCCAACCUCCAAGUCCACCAUUGAAGAAGAUCUAAAGAAACUAAUUGAUCUUGAAAGCCCAACUCCUGAAUCACAGAAGAGUUUUAAGUUCCACGCACUCUCCUCUCCUCAGUCUCCUUUCCCCAGCACCCCCACCUCACGGCGGGCCUUGCACAGAACACUGUCGGACGAGAGCAUUUACAAUAGCCAGAGGGAGCACUUUUUCACCUCCAGGGCGUCACUUCUGGACCAAGCCCUGCCCAACGACGUCCUCUUCAGUAGCACGUACCCUUCUCUCCCCAAGUCGCUCCCGUUGAGGAGGCCUUCUUACACCUUAGGAAUGAAAUCGCUGCAUGGAGAGUUCUCAGCCUCGGACAGCUCCCUCACUGACAUCCAGGAGACCCGCAGGCAGCCUAUGCCCGACCCUGGCCUGAUGCCCCUGCCUGACACUGCUGCAGACUUGGAUUGGUCCAACCUGGUAGAUGCUGCCAAAGCCUAUGAGGUCCAGAGAGCCUCAUUUUUUGCUGCUAGUGAUGAAAACCAUCGCCCCUUGAGUGCUGCAUCCAACAGUGAUCAGCUGGAGGACCAGGCUCUGGCCCAGAUGAAGCCUUACAGCAGCAGUAAAGACUCCUCUCCCACUCUGGCUUCUAAAGUGGACCAGCUGGAAGGUAUGCUGAAGAUGCUUCGGGAAGAUUUGAAGAAGGAAAAAGAAGACAAAGCUCACCUUCAGGCGGAGGUGCAGCACCUGCGAGAGGACAACCUGAGGCUACAGGAGGAGUCCCAGAACGCCUCGGACAAGCUGAAGAAGUUCACAGAAUGGGUCUUCAACACCAUAGACAUGAGCUAGGGAAGGCUGAGGAGGACAGGAGAAGGGCCCAGACACUCCCUCCAGUGAGUGUCCUGCAGCCCUUAUUCCCUCCAUAGAAAGCAUCCUCAGAGCACCUUCCCUGGCUUCCUACUCUGCCCCCUUUCGGGGAGUGCACAACACAAUAGUUGCAGAUCAACAAUCAUCACCUGCCUUUUGUAGAAAAGAAAAACAAAAAAAGUAAAUAAAAAUUUUAAACAGUAAAAUAAAAGUUUAACUGCUAAAAUGUGAAUGUCUUUAUUUUUUUGCACAAUAUCUUUAUCUGUUAUGUAUUUAAGAAGAAACUGGGCCUUGGACCAGGGCGCCCCCUGGCCCAUCCGCCUCUAUUCCCAUCAGCUUUCUUAUCAACUUCAGGUAACCCAAGCUUUCCCUUGUUAUUCUAACAAAUAUCAUUAUUCCUAGAAAAAGAAUGUUUUUAUAACUUGUUUGGGGAGUAGAGAGGGAUAUUUCCUUACCUUCUUCCCUAAAAUGCCUGGAGAGGGAGUUGCUUUGAGAAAAUGCCUACCUCCCUUGAAUGACUCGUGCAUGAGCUAGUGCUGUCUGUACCUGUCCUCCAGAGAUCAGCAGGACCGGAGUUAAAUAUUUAACAGCAAGUCUGUAAACCAGAGCAGCUCUGACAGUGCCUGCAGGCCACACCCCUUCUCAGUCCUGCAUUGUGAGGUCAUUUCCUGCUUCUCCCUUUCCCCAGGAAGAUGGUCCCACUUGUGCUGCAAGACUCUUUUUUGUUUGGCUUAAUUGAGCCCCACUAAAUUGGAAUCAAUCUCUCUUACAGCUUCCUGGCUCCAAACAUUAAUUGAUUUCAGAAUUCCCCCAAACUAAAACCUUAUCUGUCUGCAUUUUGAAUGCAUUUUGGUCAAAAGUAUACGUUUUAAAGAUUUUUAAAGAUAAAAAUGUGGCACAACUGGUUUUUUUAGCUUGCUGAAAAUGACCAUAUCUCUAAAUUAAUCUUUCUCUCCAGAGCAAGACUUCACCAGUAUUUGUAACUAGGAGAAGCUAACAGUGAAUGUUUAAUUGUGAAUUUUAAUCAUUGCUUGUUAGGAAUAAUGACUGUGAUACUAGAAUGGGCUUUUGAAACCUGCAUGUCCCAGUGUGAAAUUUCAGCACGGCAUUUUCUGCAUCCUUUCAUGGCCAUCCAAAGGAUUCCGCUGCAGAAAUUAUUGAUGUGCUAUUUUUGCUGUCUUGUGAUGCAGGCUGCUUUGGGCCCCUGGGUCACUCUUCCAAGGCUGCUGUAGAGCACAGAGACAUGGGGCUGGCCAGUGUUGACUGACCUGAGGAGACCCCUUUGUUUGUUGCCUUCAUAACUGUCACUAAACCGACCCCUCUGCCCUUUCAGUGGCAACUCUGGUCUAAGGGAACAUUCAGCACUCUAGCGGCAUCUGAUUGGAAGUUCCCUCACCCAAGUAAUCUCAAUUCCUUCCUCUCUCCAUCCCUGAAAGAAACAGGAUGGAUUUUCCUCUCUUCUCCCUGCUACAUUCACUACCAGAUUUUUAUGCUACAGUUUCAUUCUUGAUUGUGAUUUCUCCAUGGAAUUUUUUUUUUCUGGUGACAUUUCUAUCAUGGAAAUAGGAAGAUUUCGGAGUGCUUUGUGAAGAUUUCAAUUGUCUGUCUCUUUCUCUCUUUGACUUGUAUGAAGGAGAUUGUACAUUGCCUGAUAUCUCUUUGUAAAUGAGAAAUAUUGCUAACAUCCAAGCAUUCUGAAGUCUUGCUUAUCCUUCUGAGUUUAGUUCUCAUUUUGUUUUACAUUUUGUUUGGGGACUUGGGGCAAGCUAUUUAUUAGAGUUUUGCAACAGAGUUCUUGUUUGAAGCCUCUAAAGACUACCUGUAAAAUUCAAAGAAUAAAAUUCAUUUUAAACGCUCUUUUAAAACACUUUGGUAUUAUUGCUUGAGGUUUGCUUAUUUGAAAGACCACCCAAUAACUCAUUGACCCUCCUUGCAUCCGAAUUUUUUCAUCAAGCUUUGUUAACACUAAUGAUGAUUCUUGAAAAUUUCUGUCCUUCUCAGAAUGUUAAUAAACUUUUUUACUCUGUCCA